AGGUUCCAAACGCUCCGCGGCGCCAUGGGCUGAAAACUCAACCGAGAUGGAAUCUCCCAGUCUGAACCGGUUUCAACCGGUUCCGAGUUUGAGGCACUAGGAGGAGGGGGAGAAGCGGCUGCAGCGGCCGCGGCAGGAGCAGCGGGAGCUACAGCAUCAGCAAGAGCAACAGUAGCUACAGCCCCGGCGGCGGUGCCUGUUCCAGUCUUUGCUGCUGCAGUCCGUGCAACCACCCAGAGGGGGAGGGGGGAACCACCAGUCGCUGAGGAACAAGAGAAGGGGGGAAAGUUUAGGCGAGCCUUGGGGGGGGGGGGGCCAGCGCCGGAGCCGCGUGAGAGAGGGAGCCGUGUUUUGGUAGGGGGGAGUCGGACUGCAACUGGCAGCAGAGCGUCUCCCCGGCCGUGUGGACUCUACACCCCCUACUCCUGCCGCUUCUGCUGCUGCCUGUGGCUGGAGGGUCCCCCUGGGGCUGAAUCUUUGGGACUUGACCCCGUUCCCUCCCCCUUCCCUCACUCCCCAGCCGGGCGGGAGCAUUUAUUCCCCAGAUUAAUUCCCCUUUUGGGGGGGGGCGGGUGUGUGUGUGUGUGUGUGUGUGUGUGUGUGUUGGGGGAAGCGUCCCUGAAAUAGUAAAUAUUAUUGAGCUCUUUUUGCCCUUUUCCUGUCCGUUUUUUUAAUUUCCUUUUUUGAGGUGGGAAAACUGAAACCCACCUUGAUUCGUCCCCUCUCCCCCCUCCCCACCUUCCCUCGCCCUAAUCCCCCAACGAGGAAGGAAGGAGCAGUUGGUUCAAUCUCUGGAUGGAGUCUCAUUCUCUUGCCCAGGCUAGAGUGUGGUGGUGCAUCUCGGCUUACUGCAAACUCCGUCUCCUGGGUUCAAGCAGUUCUCCUGCCUCAGCUUCCCAAGUAGCUGGGAUUACAGGUGCCCGCCUCCAUGCCUGGCUGAUUUUUGUAUUUUUAGUAGAGACGGGGUUUUGCCAUGUUGGCCAGGCUGGUCUGGAACUCCUGACCUCAAGUGAUUCGCCCACCUCGGCCUCCCAAAGUGCUGGGAUUACAGUAAUCUAUGCCAGCAAUUAUGACAAUGUUAGCAGACCAUGCAGCUCGUCAGCUGCUUGAUUUCAGCCAAAAACUGGAUAUCAACUUAUUAGAUAAUGUGGUGAAUUGCUUAUACCAUGGAGAAGGAGCCCAGCAAAGAAUGGCUCAAGAAGUACUGACACAUUUAAAGGAGCAUCCUGAUGCUUGGACAAGAGUCGACACAAUUUUGGAAUUUUCUCAGAAUAUGAAUACGAAAUACUAUGGACUACAAAUUUUGGAAAAUGUGAUAAAAACAAGGUGGAAGAUUCUUCCAAGGAACCAGUGCGAAGGAAUAAAAAAAUACGUUGUUGGCCUCAUUAUCAAGACGUCAUCUGACCCAACUUGUGUAGAGAAAGAAAAGGUGUAUAUCGGAAAAUUAAAUAUGAUCCUUGUUCAGAUACUGAAACAAGAAUGGCCCAAACAUUGGCCAACUUUUAUCAGUGAUAUUGUUGGAGCAAGUAGGACCAGCGAAAGUCUCUGUCAAAAUAAUAUGGUGAUUCUUAAACUCUUGAGUGAAGAAGUAUUUGAUUUCUCUAGUGGACAGAUAACCCAAGUCAAAUCUAAGCAUUUAAAAGACAGCAUGUGCAAUGAAUUCUCACAGAUAUUUCAACUGUGUCAGUUUGUAAUGGAAAAUUCUCAAAAUGCUCCACUUGUACAUGCAACCUUGGAAACAUUGCUCAGAUUUCUGAACUGGAUUCCCCUGGGAUAUAUUUUUGAGACCAAAUUAAUCAGCACAUUGAUUUAUAAGUUCCUGAAUGUUCCAAUGUUUCGAAAUGUCUCUCUGAAGUGCCUCACUGAGAUUGCUGGUGUGAGUGUAAGCCAAUAUGAAGAACAAUUUGUAACACUAUUUACUCUGACAAUGAUGCAACUAAAGCAGAUGCUUCCUUUAAAUACCAAUAUUCGACUUGCGUACUCAAAUGGAAAAGAUGAUGAACAGAACUUCAUUCAAAAUCUCAGUUUGUUUCUCUGCACCUUUCUUAAGGAACAUGAUCAACUUAUAGAAAAAAGAUUAAAUCUCAGGGAAACUCUUAUGGAGGCCCUUCAUUAUAUGUUGUUGGUAUCUGAAGUAGAAGAAACUGAAAUCUUUAAAAUUUGUCUUGAAUACUGGAAUCAUUUGGCUGCUGAACUCUAUAGAGAGAGUCCAUUCUCUACAUCUGCCUCUCCGUUGCUUUCUGGAAGUCAACAUUUUGAUGUUCCUCCCAGGAGACAGCUAUAUUUGCCCAUGUUAUUCAAGGUCCGUUUAUUAAUGGUUAGUCGAAUGGCUAAACCAGAGGAAGUAUUGGUUGUAGAGAAUGAUCAAGGAGAAGUUGUGAGAGAAUUCAUGAAGGAUACAGAUUCCAUAAAUUUGUAUAAGAAUAUGAGGGAAACAUUGGUUUAUCUUACUCAUCUGGAUUAUGUAGAUACAGAAAGAAUAAUGACAGAGAAGCUUCACAAUCAAGUGAAUGGUACAGAGUGGUCAUGGAAAAAUUUGAAUACAUUGUGUUGGGCAAUAGGCUCCAUUAGUGGAGCAAUGCAUGAAGAGGACGAAAAACGAUUUCUUGUUACUGUUAUAAAGGAUCUAUUAGGAUUAUGUGAACAGAAAAGAGGCAAAGAUAAUAAAGCUAUUAUUGCAUCAAAUAUCAUGUACAUAGUAGGUCAAUACCCACGUUUUUUGAGAGCUCACUGGAAAUUUCUGAAGACUGUAGUUAACAAGCUGUUCGAAUUCAUGCAUGAGACCCAUGAUGGAGUCCAGGAUAUGGCUUGUGAUACUUUCAUUAAAAUAGCCCAAAAAUGCCGCAGGCAUUUCGUUCAGGUUCAGGUUGGAGAAGUGAUGCCAUUUAUUGAUGAAAUUUUGAACAACAUUAACACUAUUAUUUGUGAUCUUCAGCCUCAACAGGUUCAUACGUUUUAUGAAGCUGUGGGGUACAUGAUUGGUGCACAAACAGAUCAAACAGUACAAGAACACUUGAUAGAAAAGUACAUGUUACUCCCUAAUCAAGUGUGGGAUAGUAUAAUCCAGCAGGCAACCAAAAAUGUGGAUAUACUGAAAGAUCCUGAAACAGUCAAGCAGCUUGGUAGCAUUUUGAAAACAAAUGUGAGAGCCUGCAAAGCUGUUGGACACCCCUUUGUAAUUCAGCUUGGAAGAAUUUAUUUAGAUAUGCUUAAUGUAUACAAGUGCCUCAGUGAAAAUAUUUCUGCAGCUAUCCAAGCUAAUGGUGAAAUGGUUACAAAGCAACCAUUGAUUAGAAGUAUGCGAACUGUAAAAAGGGAAACUUUAAAGUUAAUAUCUGGUUGGGUGAGCCGAUCCAAUGAUCCACAGAUGGUCGCUGAAAAUUUUGUUCCCCCUCUGUUGGAUGCAGUUCUCAUUGAUUAUCAGAGAAAUGUCCCAGCUGCUAGAGAACCAGAAGUGCUUAGUACUAUGGCCAUAAUUGUCAACAAGUUAGGGGGACAUAUAACAGCUGAAAUACCUCAAAUAUUUGAUGCUGUUUUUGAAUGCACAUUGAAUAUGAUAAAUAAGGACUUUGAAGAAUAUCCUGAACAUAGAACGAACUUUUUCUUACUACUUCAGGCUGUCAAUUCUCAUUGUUUCCCAGCAUUCCUUGCUAUUCCACCUACACAGUUUAAACUUGUUUUGGAUUCCAUCAUUUGGGCUUUCAAACAUACUAUGAGGAAUGUCGCAGAUACGGGCUUACAGAUACUUUUUACACUCUUACAAAAUGUUGCACAAGAAGAAGCUGCAGCUCAGAGUUUUUAUCAAACUUAUUUUUGUGAUAUUCUCCAGCAUAUCUUUUCUGUUGUGACAGACACUUCACAUACUGCUGGUUUAACAAUGCAUGCAUCAAUUCUUGCAUAUAUGUUUAAUUUGGUUGAAGAAGGAAAAAUAAGUACAUCAUUAAAUCCUGGAAAUCCAGUUAACAACCAAAUCUUUCUUCAGGAAUAUGUGGCUAAUCUCCUUAAGUCGGCCUUCCCUCACCUACAAGAUGCUCAAGUAAAGCUCUUUGUGACAGGGCUUUUCAGCUUAAAUCAAGAUAUUCCUGCUUUCAAGGAACAUUUAAGAGAUUUCCUAGUUCAAAUAAAGGAAUUUGCAGGUGAAGACACUUCUGAUUUGUUUUUGGAAGAGAGAGAAAUAGCCCUACGGCAGGCUGAUGAAGAGAAACAUAAACGUCAAAUGUCUGUCCCUGGCAUCUUUAAUCCACAUGAGAUUCCAGAAGAAAUGUGUGAUUAAAAUCCAAAUUCAUGCUGUUUUUUUUCUCUGCAACUCGUUAGCAGAGGAAAACAGCAUGUGGGUAUUUGUCGACCAAAAUGAUGCCAAUUUGUAAAUUAAAAUGUCACCUAGUGGCCCUUUUUCUUAUGUGUUUUUUUGUAUAAGAAAUUUUCUGUGAAAUAUCCUUCCAUUGUUUAAGCUUUUGUUUUGGUCAUCUUUAUUUAGUUUGCAUGAAGUUGAAAAUUAAGGCAUUUUUAAAAAUUUUACUUCAUGCCCAUUUUUGUGGCUGGGCUGGGGGGAGGAGGCAAAUUCGAUUUGAACAUAUACUUGUAAUUCUAAUGCAAAAUUAUACAAUUUUUCCUGUAAACAAUACCAAUUUUUAAUUAGGGAGCAUUUUCCUUCUAGUCUAUUUCAGCCUAGAAGAAAAGAUAAUGAGUAAAACAAAUUGCGUUGUUUAAAGGAUUAUAGUGCUGCAUUGUCUGAAGUUAGCACCUCUUGGACUGAAUCGUUUGUCUAGACUACAUGUAUUACAAAGUCUCUUUGGCAAGAUUGCAGCAAGAUCAUGUGCAUAUCAUCCCAUUGUAAAGCGACUUCAAAAAUAUGGGAACACAGUUAGUUAUUUUUACACAGUUCUUUUUGUUUUUGUGUGUGUGUGCUGUCGCUUGUCGACAACAGCUUUUUGUUUUCCUCAAUGAGGAGUGUUGCUCAUUUGUGAGCCUUCAUUAACUCGAAGUGAAAUGGUUAAAAAUAUUUAUCCUGUUAGAAUAGGCUGCAUCUUUUUAACAACUCAUUAAAAAACAAAACAACUCUGGCUUUUGAGAUGACUUAUACUAAUUUACAUUGUUUACCAAGCUGUAGUGCUUUAAGAACACUACUUAAAAAGCAAAAUAAACUUGGUUUACAUUUAUUUUUCCUUUAUUGACUCAUUUAUUCCUAUAUUAAUGAUAGUGGGUAUUUGUGUUUAAGCAUCAAGUAACAUUUUAAAUGAAGUU